AAACUCCGCAGUGCUCAGCCAAGCAGGGAGCAACGCUAGGAAGGGCGGGCAGAAAGGGCACGCUCUUGUGGGUGACUACAGGUUAGGAGACCGUUGAACCUGGAGGGGCCCUAGGAUGGACCCCGUGGAAAGAUUCAGAGACUGCGCCCUCUCCCUGGCGCCGCCUUCCCCUACACGCGGCGGGUAUAUUCUGUUGCAGUUGGCCCAGGACCUGUUUCCAAGACUCUGCCCCCUCGCACUUCCGUCCCUCCUGGUUUUGUAAAGUGAUGCUCAUAGGAACCCCCACCCCGCGUGACACUACUCCCAGCUCCUGGCUGACUUCUAGUCUUCUGGUUGAAGCUGCGCCUUUAGAUGACACGACCCUACCCACCCCUGUUUCCAGCGGAUGCCCGGGCCUGGAGCCCACAGAAUUCUUCCAGUCCCUGGGUGGGGACGGAGAAAGGAACGUUCAGAUUGAGAUGGCCCAUGGCACCACCACGCUCGCCUUCAAGUUCCAGCAUGGAGUGAUUGCAGCAGUGGAUUCUCGGGCCUCAGCUGGGUCCUACAUUAGUGCCUUACGGGUGAACAAGGUGAUUGAGAUUAACCCUUACCUGCUUGGCACCAUGUCUGGCUGUGCAGCAGACUGUCAGUACUGGGAGCGCCUGCUGGCCAAGGAAUGCAGGCUGUACUAUCUGCGAAAUGGAGAACGUAUUUCAGUGUCGGCAGCCUCCAAGCUGCUGUCCAACAUGAUGUGCCAGUACCGGGGCAUGGGCCUCUCUAUGGGCAGUAUGAUCUGUGGCUGGGAUAAGAAGGGUCCUGGACUCUACUACGUGGAUGAACAUGGGACUCGGCUCUCAGGAAAUAUGUUCUCCACGGGUAGUGGGAACACUUAUGCCUACGGGGUCAUGGACAGUGGCUAUCGGCCUAAUCUUAGCCCUGAAGAGGCCUAUGACCUUGGCCGCAGGGCUAUUGCUUAUGCCACUCACAGAGACAGCUAUUCUGGAGGCGUUGUCAAUAUGUACCACAUGAAGGAAGAUGGUUGGGUGAAAGUAGAAAGUACAGAUGUCAGUGACCUGCUGCACCAGUACCGGGAAGCCAAUCAAUAAUGGUGGUGGUGGCAGCUGGGCAGGUCUCCUCUGGGAGGUCUUGGCCGACUCAGGGACCUAAGCCACGUUAAGUCCAAGGAGAAGAAGAGGCCUAGCCUGAGCCAAAGAGAGAGUACGGGCUCAGCAGCCAGAGGAGGCCGGUGAAGUGCAUCUUCUGCGUGUUCUCUAUUUGAACAAGCAUUUCCCCCAGGGAAGUUUCUGGGUGCCCCACUAAGUAGAAUAAAGAAAAACGGUUAUAAAUA